GGGCUUAAUGACGGAAGGAGCAUGGCGUGGAGACACCUGAAAGUGAGUCCCGCGAGUGAGCAGUGUGGAUGGGGGACCAGGGACCGGGGAGGGCGAGAACGGAGAGUCAGGCCGGGCGAGGCAUGGACCGAAGGCGGCUCCGGGAGUGUGGGCCCCCCUGGGACGUAAGCGGGCCCAGGAUGCUGUGAUCAUCCUGGGGGGAGGAGGACUUCUCUUCGCCUCCUACCUGAUGGCCACGGGAGAUGAGCGUUUCUAUGCUGAACACCUGAUGCCGACUCUGCAGGGGCUGCUGGACCCGGAGUCAGCCCACAGACUGGCUGUUCGCUUCACCUCCCUGGGGCUCCUUCCACGGGCCAGAUUUCAAGACUCUGACAUGCUGGAAGUGAGAGUUCUGGGCCAUAAAUUCCGAAAUCCAGUAGGAAUUGCUGCAGGAUUUGACAAGCAUGGGGAAGCCGUGGACGGACUUUAUAAGAUGGGCUUUGGUUUUGUUGAGAUAGGAAGUGUGACUCCAAAACCUCAGGAAGGAAACCCUAGACCCAGAGUCUUCCGCCUCCCUGAGGACCAAGCUGUCAUUAACAGGUAUGGAUUUAACAGUCACGGGCUUUCAGUGGUGGAACACAGGUUACGGGCCAGACAGCAGAAGCAGGCCAAGCUCACAGAAGAUGGACUGCCUCUGGGGGUCAACUUGGGGAAGAACAAGACCUCAGUGGACGCCGCGGAGGACUACGCAGAAGGGGUGCGCGUACUGGGCCCCCUGGCCGACUACCUGGUGGUGAAUGUGUCCAGCCCCAACACUGCCGGGCUGCGGAGCCUUCAGGGAAAGGCCGAGCUGCGCCGCCUGCUGACCAAGGUGCUGCAGGAGAGGGAUGGCUUGCGGAGAGUGCACAGGCCGGCAGUCCUGGUGAAGAUCGCUCCUGACCUCACCAGCCAGGAUAAGGAGGACAUUGCCAGUGUGGUCAAAGAGUUGGGCAUCGAUGGGCUGAUUGUUACGAACACCACCGUGAGUCGCCCUGCGGGCCUCCAGGGUGCCCUGCGCUCUGAAACAGGAGGGCUGAGUGGGAAGCCCCUCCGGGAUUUAUCAACUCAAACCAUUCGGGAGAUGUAUGCACUCACCCAAGGCCGAGUUCCCAUAAUUGGGGUUGGUGGUGUGAGCAGCGGGCAGGACGCGCUGGAGAAGAUCCGGGCAGGGGCCUCCCUGGUGCAGCUGUACACGGCCCUCACCUUCUGGGGGCCACCCGUUGUGGGCAAAGUCAAGCGGGAACUGGAGGCCCUUCUGAAAGAGCAGGGCUUUGGCGGAGUCACAGAUGCCAUUGGAGCAGAUCAUCGGAGGUGAGGACAGCGUCUGACGGGAAGCCUGAUCUGGAACCUUCCCAAGGACUCAGGCAAGCCUUUGUGGCUGGAUCAUGAGAGGAGGGACUCCAUCUUGAGCCAUGUCCCCCAGCCAUGGCAUGGCUGCACUGUAAACGCCAAUCGGGGGGUCACCAGGAUCAACCGCAGGCUUUCUUCAGUCCCUUGGUCAGACCAUAAACUGCAUUUUUGAUUCUUUGUGGAUUCAAACCCUAGGAUCCAUCAGUCUUGCAAGGACAUUGAAUAUUAGGAGGAAAAAGUCAUGGAAAAAAUAAAGCCAUUUAGAACCUGGGUUUCAACGCUAGCCCUUUCUGGUUUGCCAUAGGCCCUGCCAAGAUACUGCAGGUCCAUCCAGGCCUCUGCUAUCUGCAUCUGCAGUGGGCUUCCCAGGAACUUGACUGUCUUUCAUUUGAUCUUUAUUUUUGUUUAUUUAAUAUUUUAAACUUUAUUUUAAAAAUAUUUCAAACAUAAGGGCGGGGUGUGGUGGCUCAUGCCUGUAAUCCCAGCACUUUGGGAGGCCGAGGCGGGCGGAUCACCUGAGGCCAGGAGUUGGAGACCAGCCAGGCCACCAUGGUGAAACCCUGUCUCUACCAAAAAUACAAAAAAUUAGCCAGAUAUUGUGGCAGGCACUUUUAAUCCCAGCUACUCGGGAGGCUGAGGCAGGAGAAUUGCUUGAACCUGGGAGGCGGAGGUUGCAGUGAGCCAAGAUUGCACCAGUGCACUCCAGCUUGGGCGACAGAUCAAGACUCUGUCACACACAAAACAAACAAACAAAUUUUCCCGUUUCUCUCUGUCCCUUUCUCUAUAACAUGGAUAAAAUAUUCACGUCUUAUGUAUUUAUUAUUGCUGAGUCAUUGGUGCCUUAUUCUUCAGUGUUUCAGUCUGUAUCUCCUAAGCAUCCUGAUGUUAGUUUUUUGACUAUAAAAUUGACCUGCAUUCUUUACUAGCAAUUCAAACGGUACAGCACUCUUGAAGUGUAAACAUUCCUGUUCCUCCUCACCCCACUCUGCAGACAUGCCUUUCUGUCUGUCCUCCCAGACUUUUCCCCUGCAUAAAGAUGUUCAUUUUGUACAUACACUCAGACAUACAUGUGGCUGUAUUUUUUGUAUACCGAUUUCUGGAUGGAAUGCACACUGUUAUCUGUUUAGUUACUUUAUGUUUUCAUACAAAUGACAUCAUCCCACAAAUAGAAUUCUGCCAUUUACUUUCUUCACUAUUCUUAUGUGGCAUGGUUCAUGCUGGGCCUCGGUCUUUUGAGUGGGGUCUGUUUACCCAGUCCCCUGUUGGUGAUCACAUCGCUAACUUCCGGCGUUUUCCUAUCACCAUCGGUGCCUCCGUGAACACCUUGUGAAUGUGCCUGUGCCUUCGUUCUGGUGUCGGUGCAGAGCAGGGUCCAAGGGGCGUGACAGCUGGGCUGAGGGGCUGGCAUGUUUCACAUUCUGAUAGAUAGAGCCAAGUUGCUCCUAUCAGGUUUUCAAGCUGCCCAUUUCCCACCGUGGAGACAGCAACAGAGGGGACAUCCCCAGCUCCUCUGGCUCUGCCUGUUCAAAGCUACCCUGUGAGGCCUGAAGACAGAGCUGCCCUGAAGGCAGCUCAUGUCCACUGAACACUGACUGUGGGCUGGAUGCUGUGCCAAGGGCUUGACGUUUCCUCUUUAAGGAUGAGGAAACGGGCAGAGAAGCGGCUGAUUGUCCAGUCCCCCUGCGUGGAGGCUGCUUGGCUGGGCUCGAGCCCAGCGGUGUGGUCAUAGAGCAUGUUGUGCUGAAUGGCUCUGCCAUGGACCAAGCCUUGGCUGCUCUAAAAGCCGGCUCAUUGCCUUCUGCUUCUCCGGAUUCGUUCCUUACUCCAGGAAGAGCAGUGCACUGAAGGAGAAAUGGGAAUGGGCAAAAGGAACCACAUGCUGGCCAGACCCCUGCGGGGUCACUUUCCUCAGCCUGGGCUCCGACAUGCCACGUCAGGUGCCAGCGCACAUACUCUGGACACCCUCCUCAUUCUCUCUGGGCUUUGAUGCUCUCUGUGAGUCAUCUGCCCUCCCUUUCCCAUGCUACAGGCAUCUACCUUGCUCUGUCCCACCUAAUAGCUUCAGGACUGAACAAUUCAGGAAAGGGAAGGGAAGGGGUGGAGGAGAAGAGGGAAGAGUCGGCCCUUGGAAGGUUCUCCACGGAAGACUGCCUUUUUUUUUUUUGAGAUGGAGUCUCGCUGUGUCGCCCAGCCUGGAGUGCAGUGGCAUGAUCUCAGCUCACUGCAAACUCCGCCUCCUGGGUUCAGGGGAUUCUUCAGCCUCAGCCUCCAGAGUAGCUGGGACUACAGGUGCAUGCCACUGUGCCCUGCUAAUUUUUGUAUUUUUAGUAGAGACGGGGUUUCACCAUAUUGGCCAGGCUGGUCUCGAACUCCUGACCUCUUGGUCCACCCGCCUCAGCCUCCCAAAGUGCUGGGAUUACAGGUGCAAGCCACCGCGCCUGGCUCGAGAGACUGACAUUCUGUCUCAGCACAGCUGGAAGAGGCUGCUUGAGCACCAGGAUAAGGAGUUGUCUUGCAUUCAGGGGCCAUGUGGUGUGCGGAUACCUAUUUUUCUUUCUUUUCUUUUUUUUUUCUGAGACAGAGUCUCGCUCUGUCUCCCAGGCUAGAGUGCAGUGGCAUGAUCUCAGCUCACUGCAACCUCUGUCUCCCGGGUUCAAGCAAUUCUUCUGCCUCAGCCUCCCAAGUAGCUGGGAUUACAGGUGCCCACUACCACACCCAGCUAAUUUGUGUGUGUGUGUGUGUGUGUGUGUGUGUGUGUGUGUGUGUGUGUGUGUGUUUUUGAGAUGGAGUCCUGCUCUGUCACCCCGGCUGGAGUGCAGUGGUGCGAUCUCAGCUCACUGCAAGCUCCGCCUCCCGGGUUCACACUAUUCUCCUGCCUCAGCCUCCCGAGUAGCUGGGACUACAGGCGCCUGCCACCAUGCCUGGCUAGUUUUUUUGUAUUUUAAGUAGAGACAGGGUUUCACCGUGUUAGCCAGGAUGGUUCGAUCUCCUGACCUCAUGAUCUGGCCGCCUCAGUCUCCCAAAGUGCUGAGAUUACAGGCGUGAGCCAGCGUGCCUGGCUAAUUUUUGUAUUUUUAGUAGAGACGGGGUUUCACCAUGUUGGCCAGGCUGGUCUCGAACCCCUGACCUCAAGCAAUCCACCCACCUUGGCCUCCCAAAGAGCUGAGAUUACAGGUGUGAGCCACCGCACCCGGCCCAAGGAUACCUAUUUUUCUUAAUGCUGGAAGCCACACUCAGACACCAGAGCAGCUCUCAAUGCUGGGAAUCCUGGGAGACUGAUGAUGACCGCGUCUCCCUCUGGGACCAAGGAUGGUGGAAGGGUGUGCAGAAUUCCAAAUGUUAUUUACAUCACUCACUCUUGUGUGGAGUGCAUAAUUGUCUUUGCUUGCCAAUUUCAUAUCAGUUAAAUAUAAGCAGUAAGCUAA